GCCCCAGACCUUGGAGCUGUUGUCCCACCCCUGUCACUGCAGAGAGCUGAGGCACCAUGCAUGGGGGCCAGGGGCCGCUGCUCCUCCUGCUGCUGCUGGCUGUCUGCCUGGGGGCCCAGGGCCGGAACCAGGAGGAGCGCCUGCUCGCAGACCUGAUGCAAAACUACGACCCCAACCUGCGGCCCGCGGAACGAGACUCGGAUGUGGUCAAUGUCAGCCUGAAGCUAACCCUCACCAACCUCAUCUCCCUGAACGAGCGAGAGGAAGCCCUCACCACCAAUGUCUGGAUAGAGAUGCAGUGGUGCGACUAUCGCCUGCGCUGGGAUCCGCGAGACUACGAAGGCCUGUGGGUGCUGAGGGUGCCGUCCACCAUGGUGUGGCGGCCGGAUAUCGUGCUGGAGAACAACGUGGACGGUGUCUUCGAGGUGGCCCUCUACUGCAAUGUGCUCGUGUCCCCUGACGGCUGUAUCUACUGGCUGCCGCCUGCCAUCUUCCGUUCCGCCUGCUCUAUCUCAGUCACCUACUUCCCCUUCGACUGGCAGAACUGCUCCCUUAUCUUCCAGUCCCAGACUUACAGCACCAAUGAGAUUGAUCUGCAGCUGAGUCAGGAAGAUGGCCAGACCAUCGAGUGGAUUUUCAUUGACCCUGAGGCCUUCACAGAGAAUGGGGAGUGGGCCAUCCAGCACCGACCAGCCAAGAUGCUCCUGGACCCAGCGGCGCCAGCCCAGGAAGCAGGCCACCAGAAGGUGGUGUUCUACCUGCUCAUCCAGCGCAAGCCCCUCUUCUACGUCAUCAACAUCAUCGCCCCCUGUGUGCUCAUCUCCUCUGUCGCCAUCCUCAUCCACUUCCUUCCUGCCAAGGCUGGGGGCCAGAAGUGUACCGUCGCCAUCAACGUGCUCCUGGCCCAGACUGUCUUCCUCUUCCUUGUGGCCAAGAAGGUGCCUGAAACCUCCCAGGCGGUGCCACUCAUCAGCAAGUACCUGACCUUCCUCCUGGUGGUGACCAUCCUCAUUGUCGUGAAUGCUGUGGUUGUGCUCAAUGUCUCCUUGCGGUCUCCACACACACACUCCAUGGCCCGAGGGGUCCGCAAGGUGUUCCUGAGGCUCUUGCCCCAGCUGCUGAGGAUGCACGUUCGCCCGCUGGCCCCGGCAGCUGUGCAGGACACCCAGUCCCGGCUACAGAAUGGCUCCUCGGGAUGGUCGAUCACAACUGGGGAGGAGGUGGCCCUCUGCCUGCCUCGCAGUGAACUCCUCUUCCAGCAGUGGCAGCGGCAAGGGCUGGUGGCGGCAGCGCUGGAGAAGCUAGAGAAAGGCCCGGAGUUAGGGCUGAGCCAGUUCUGUGGCAGCCUGAAGCAGGCUGCCCCAGCCAUCCAGGCCUGUGUGGAAGCCUGCAACCUCAUUGCCUGUGCCCGGCACCAGCAGAGUCACUUUGACAAUGGGAAUGAGGAGUGGUUCCUGGUGGGCCGAGUGCUGGACCGCGUCUGCUUCCUGGCCAUGCUCUCGCUCUUCAUCUGUGGCACAGCUGGCAUCUUCCUCAUGGCCCACUACAACCGGGUGCCGGCCCUGCCAUUCCCUGGAGAUCCACGCCCCUACCUGCCCUCACCAGACUGAGCCAACCAACCACUGUGGGGCAUGUGGGAGUCACACACGUGGGUCACACUGAGUCUUAUCAGCCACGUUCUCCUACUGAGGUCCUAAGUGUGCUCUUUGGGAAGUGCCCUUCAGGACUGUGUGAGCCAAACAGCCCUGAGAAAAGCUGGGGAAACAGUCUGAGCUGGAGUCCGAGAGUGGUUGGGGGUGGGCCGUGGCUAGUGUCCUGCUGCAGUCAGCACACACGUGGGAUUGGCUAGCUCAUCCUGGCACCAGCCACCCCUCCACUCAGUGCACUCCCCUCACUUAGGCAAAGCAUUAUUCAUUCCCAUCAGUCUGAAGCCCGAAGGACUGUUUUGUAUAAUACCUUCGGACUUGGGACUGGCUCCCCUUUUACAAGUUCUCCCUGAAAGAGGGCAGUCACAAGAGGUGUGAAGAGUAGCAGCCGAUGCUCUCUCCAAAGCAGGGCAGCAGCCCAUACCAGCUGGCAUCUCCCCCCCGUGCCUUCUGGGUACAAUAAGCACCCAAUUCUCAACAGCCCCAGUGGCCUUUCCAUUCAUGUGCAUUUUUCUGCCACUGACCACAAGACGAUUUCCUGAGUUUUGUAAUCCUCUUUUUUUUUUUUUUUUUUUUAGUUUUUGAUGUGUUGUUGUUGUUUUGUUUAGUUUUGAGAUAGAGCCUCACUCUUGUCAUGCAAGUUGGAGUGGAGUGGCAUGAUCAUGGCUCACUGCAGCCUCAACCUCCAGGGCUCAAGCAAUGCUCCUGCCUCAGCCUCCCAAGUAGCUGGCACCACAGGCAUGCACCACUACACCCAGCUACUUUUAAAUUUUUAGUAGAGAUGAGGUUUUGCUAUGUUGCCUAGGUUGGUCUUGAACUCCUGAGCUCAAGUGAUCCUCCCACUUGAGUCUUGGGAUUACAGGCAUAAGCCACUGUACCUGGCCUCCUUUUUAAUUAAGAGCUCCUCACAGCAGUAUGGAUAAGCAAGAGUCAUUAUUCCCCAUGUUAUAUAGGCAAAUUGAGCCUAGAGUAAGCGGGACUCCACACAACAGUGGUGGUUAAACAAGGUUUGAAGUCCAGAAUUCCUGACUCUGACCCAAUCUGACACUCUAAGAUUCUACGGCCUGAAAAACAGGCCCUUCUUCCCAAAGGAUGGUUAAGACAAGGAAGAGCUAGGCAAGAGGAGGUGUGGAGUUAACAGAGAGCCACUGAGCUCUUCAUUCCAGGAGGAGACUUUGACUGGCCUCCCUUGACCCCACUAAUCAGGUAGUAAGGCUGGGGUCUUCCUGGGGGAGAGGCAAGGUCCUGCUCUGAGAUUACAGCCGGCACACGAGUUUGGCUGGUAACCAGGGGACACCCUUGGGCAAGUCACCUAUGCUCCCUGAGGCUGUUCCCUCAUCUGUAAAUAAGGUGCAAAAAAUAAUCCAUUCCUGGCCAGGUGUGGUGGCUCACACCUGCAAUCCCAGCACCUUGGGAGGACAAGGUGGGUGGACUGCUUGAGCUCAGGAGCCCACGAACCCAGGAACCCAGCCUGGGCAACAUGGGGACACCCGGCCUCUACCAAAAAAUACAAAACUUAGCUGGGCGUGGUGAUGCAUGCCUGUAGUCCCAGUUACUCGGGAGGCUGAGGUGGGAGGAUCGCUUGAGCCCAGGAGGUCUAGGCUGCAGUGAGCUGUGAUCAUGUGACUGCACUCCAGCCUGAUGACACAGUAAGACCCUGUCUCAAAAAAAAUAAAAAAAUUACAAAACUGAAAAAAGAAAAGUGAAAGUGCCACAUAAAGGCCUGACGACAGGAUAUGCUGGCAGGAGGGGACCUUGGAAAUAUGCCCUCCCUCCAAGCACAGGAUUGCUGUCUUUGGGAUUCAAUCACCAGCAAGUUCGUAUUAUUUACUCCAGUGUGAGUCUGUGUCUGUGCAUGCACAGUGUGUUUGAAGCAAGAGCAGAGUCAGAGCUAUAGAGAACUAGAGGAGUUAGGGAGAGUGGGGGAGAACUUCAAUCAGGGAGGGAAUCUGAUGACAGUGGGGCCAUUUCCGGUUCCCACCAGCCCCUUACUAGUUGUGUAUCUGGCACAAGUCUCUCAACCUCUCUGAAAGCCUCAGAGGGCAGAGGAUUAGCUCCUUGUACACAAUAAACACUCAAAUGUUAACAUUAGCUGCCAUUACUAUAAGUUACUGUCUCAUGGGAUCCAUACAGCAACCUAAGGAGGUAGGUCGAGGCAUACCUCAAAGACAUUGCAGGUUCAGUUCCAGACCAACACAAGAAAGCAAGUCACAUGAAUGUUUUUGGUUUCCCAAUGCAUAUAAAAGUUAUGUUUACACUAUACUGUAGACCAGCAAGAGUGCAAUAGCAUUGUCUAAUAAAACAAUAUACAUACCUAAAUUUAAAAAUACUUUAUUGCUAAAAAAUGCUGAUUAUCAAUCUGA